GUGCGCAGGCGCGCCGACAGCCGAGUUUUCUGCGCUUCCUUCUCCCUCUCUCCAGACGUCGUGGUCGUUCGGUCCUAUGUCGCGCCGGGCCCUCCGGAGGCUGAGGGGGGAACAGCGCGGCCAGGAGCCCCUCGGGCCCGGCGCCUUGCAUUUCGAUCUCCGUGAUGACGAUGACGCGGAAGAAGAAGGGCCCAAGCGGGAGCUUGGUGUCCGGCGUCCCGGGGGCGCAGGGAAGGAGGGCGUCCGAGUCAACAACCGCUUCGAGCUGAUAAACAUUGACGAUCUUGAGGAUGACCCUGUGGUGAACGGGGAGAGGUCUGGCUGUGCGCUCACAGACGCUGUGGCACCAGGGAACAAAGGAAGGGGUCAGCGUGGAAACACAGAGAGCAAGACGGAUGGAGAUGACACCGAGACAGUGCCCUCAGAGCAGUCUCAUGCAAGUGGCAAACUCCGGAAGAAGAAAAAAAAACAGAAAAACAAGAAAAGCAGCACGGGAGAAGCAUCGGAAAACGGACUAGAAGAUAUCGAUCGCAUCCUAGAGAGGAUUGAGGACAGCACUGGGUUGAACCGUCCCGGCCCAGCUCCCCUGAGCUCCAGGAAGCACGUUCUCUACGUGGAGCACAGACACUUGAAUCCAGACACAGAACUGAAAAGGUAUUUUGGUGCCCGGGCAAUCCUGGGGGAGCAAAGGCCACGGCAGAGACAACGUGUGUACCCCAAGUGCACAUGGCUGACCACCCCUAAAAGCACCUGGCCCCGCUACAGCAAACCAGGUCUGUCCAUGCGGCUGCUGGAAUCAAAAAAAGGCCUCUCCUUCUUUGCGUUUGAGCACAGUGAGGAGUACCAGCAGGCUCAGCACAAGUUCCUGGUGGCCGUGGAGUCUAUGGAGCCGAACAACAUCGUGGUUCUGCUCCAGACGAGCCCUUACCACGUUGACUCACUCCUGCAGCUCAGCGAUGCCUGCCGCUUUCAAGAGGAUCAGGAGAUGGCUCGAGACCUCGUAGAGAGAGCGCUGUACAGCAUGGAAUGUGCGUUCCACCCCCUGUUCAGUCUCACCAGUGGGGCCUGCCGGCUGGAUUACCGCAGACCCGAGAACAGGAGCUUCUACCUGGCCCUCUACAAGCAGAUGAGCUUCCUGGAGAAGCGAGGCUGCCCGCGCACGGCGCUGGAGUACUGCAAGCUCAUCCUGAGUCUCGAGCCGGAUGAGGACCCCCUCUGCAUGCUGCUGCUCAUCGACCACCUGGCCUUGCGGGCCCGGAACUACGAGUACCUGAUCCGCCUCUUCCAGGAGUGGGAGGCUCAUCGGAACCUGUCCCAGCUCCCUAAUUUUGCCUUCUCUGUUCCACUGGCGUAUUUCCUGCUGAGCCAGCAGACAGACCUCCCUGAGUGUGAGCAGAGCUCUGCCAGGCAGAAGGCCUCUCUCCUGAUACAGCAGGCGCUCACCAUGUUCCCUGGAGUCCUCCUGCCCCUGCUCGAGUCUUGCAGUGUGCGGCCCGACGCCAGCGUUUCCAGUCACCGCUUCUUUGGACCCAAUGCUGAAAUAAGCCAGCCCCCUGCCCUGAGCCAGCUGGUGAACCUGUACCUUGGGAGGUCACACUUUCUCUGGAAAGAGCCCGCCACCAUGAGCUGGCUGGAGGAGAACGUCCACGAGGUUCUGCAAGCAGUGGACGCCGGGGACCCAGCCGUGGAAGCCUGUGAGAACCGGCGGAAGGUGCUCUACCAGCGUGCACCCAGGAAUAUCCACCGCCAUGUGAUCCUCUCUGAGAUCAAGGAAGCCGUCGCUGCCCUGCCCCCGGACGUGACCACGCAGUCUGUGAUGGGGUUUGAUCCUCUGCCUCCUUCGGACACAAUCUACUCCUACGUCAGGCCAGAGAGGCUAAGUCCUAUCAGCCAUGGAAACACCAUUGCUCUCUUCUUCCGGUCACUGUUGCCAAACUAUACCAUGGAGGGGGAGAGGCCCGAGGAAGGAGUGGCUGGGGGUCUGAACCGCAACCAGGGCCUGAACAGGCUGAUGCUGGCUGUGCGCGACAUGAUGGCCAACUUCCACCUCAACGACCUGGAGGCGCCGCACGAGGACGACGCUGAGGGGGAGGGGGAGUGGGACUGAGCGUCCGCAGAGGUGACCGAAAAGCCGUAUGAUGAUGUUCCCGAUUUCUCUGUUGGUCGGAGUCGGCCAGUUGCCUGAAGUAGGGAAGCUGAGUGUGUCGCUCCCUGGUCCACUGUUUCUCCUAUAAAUGUAAAUGGGUCA